GUCCACUGCACCUCCUGAGAGUUCGCCGGCCCGGGCCCCAAUGGGCUUGUUCCAAGGGGUCAUGCAGAAAUACAGCAGCAGCUUGUUCAAGACCUCCCAGCUGGCGUAAGUGACUCCUGUCUGGCCCCAGGACCAUCCAAGUUCACUCCGCUAACUGGGAUGGCAGGGAGGGUGGGAAGCAGGCCCACAGCCCCCAGGAGGGCAGAGGGCACUAUGGAGGCACCUGCCAGGCACGCUCCUUCUAGGGGUGCCCCCCUGGGGCCCCACUGCUCCUGCUGAGAUGGGCUUGGUGGCCACAGACUUCAGUCCUCAAGGAACUUCCAGCCAGGCAUGCUGGUGAUCCCCCCCUCAGAUGCCCCCAGCAUGGGACCUGAGUGCUGGAGGAGCCCCAUGGGGCUCUGAAACUGGGGACCCAGCACGAGGGAAAUUGGGGAGAUGGCCUUAGAACCCCAGAGGCCCAGGAGAGCUUGGAGUUGAACUUGAUGAGUUGGCUGCACCCUUCUGUUUGUCCCAGUCUCACUUUCCCCCAUGCCAUCGCUGUGGGUACAUCCAAAAUGCCCACACCCACAGCCUUUGUUUUGUUUAUUUGCCCUUAUUUGUGAAGUGCCAGGUGCUAAAAUCCAGAAAUAAUCUAAGCUGCAGGGGCUCUGUUUGCCUGGCACCAGGGGGCAGGGCUAAUGCGCUCCUUAGAAAAUAAUUCUGCCUCCCUCCCCUCUCUGUACCCCUGGAAUAGUGACCCCGGAAGCAGCCAAAAGCAAAAGAGGGACCCUAUCACUGGAACUGCAUUUCCUCACUCAGUUACGUUGUAGAGAAGGGAGGAGGCAAUUGGCCAAUAUUUUCUUUCUCCUUCCCAGCCUUUUUCAAAUCCUGUCGCCCUCCACUUCCUUGGUGUGGUGGGUGUGUGGAGUGGUUGACAAUCUGGAAAAGGGAGACCCAGAGCUGGUCUCAGCUACUGCCACCUCCUGCAUGACUGCCUGAGAGUCGCUGUCCCCUCUGAGUCUCCCUUCUCUGCAGGACACGGCUGGAGAGGGCAACGUGACCUCUAGGGUCCCGUCCAGCUUACUACUCUGAUGGCCUGACACCCCCAGAACCCUCCCCCACUCAUAGGGCGGGGACUUUGCCUGAGGUCAUGGAGAAGCUGUGAAUAUGUGGGCUGAGGGCUCCAGGGUCCUUGCAUCACAGCUGGAGAGACCCAAGCUGGGCGGCAGGUCCUGAAAGUGUUCUCACGACACUGCACCACGCCCUGCUCGCCAAGGCCACGAGAAAAGCCAGCCCUCCUCCCUUCCACUUCAGCUGGGGUCCCUUUGGAGACACUCCAGGAAAAGGGGGGCACAUACCCCCACUGGGCUUUUCCUGAUGCUGACAGGGGCUGCUCUGGCUGUUCCUAAGUGGAACUCGUCAAGGUGGCAGUGACGGUGCUGAUGGGGACCUCAGGACUUAUCUGAUCAGUUUCCCAUCGUCCUUGCUGGGUCUGUUGCUUCACCGGCAUCUGUGCUCUGACACCAUUAAUAACCACAGAGUCUGAGAGUCAGGAGGAAGUGCUGCUCACGCUGGAGGAAGUGGCUGGGAGAGUGCAGGGGCUGGUGGCAGAGACCGCCCAGAGCCCAUCCUAGCCCAACAUGGCGUGGGUGUCCUGGGAAUGAGGCCUGCCUCCAGCCUCACCUUCUCCAUCUGGGAAAUGGGACUAUUGAUGCAGAAGCCUCCCCAAAAGUGGAUCUGAGAGGCAUAGACAUCGUGGUUCUCACGGACUCUCCAAGGAUGAGGCCUGCGGACCCCUUGAUAAAGGCCAUCAAGGAUGGCGAUGAAGAGGCCUUGAAGACCAUGAUCAAGGAAGGGAAGAAUCUCGCAGAGCCCAACAAGGAGGGCUGGCUGCCGCUGCACGAGGCCGCAUACUAUGGCCAGGUGGGCUGCCUGAAAGUCCUGCAGCGAGCGUACCCAGGGACCAUCGACCAGCGCACCCUGCAGGAGGAAACAGCCGUUUACUUGGCAACGUGCAGGGGCCACCUGGACUGUCUCCUGUCACUGCUCCAAGCAGGGGCAGAGCCGGACAUCUCCAACAAAUCCCGAGAGACACCGCUCUACAAAGCCUGCGAGCGCAAGAACGCGGAGGCCGUGAAGAUUCUGGUGCAGCACAAUGCAGACACCAACCACCGCUGCAACCGCGGCUGGACCGCUCUGCACGAGUCUGUGUCUCGCAAUGACCUGGAGGUCAUGCAGAUCCUGGUGAGCGGAGGAGCCAAGGUGGAAUCCAAGAACGCCUACGGCAUCACCCCCUUGUUCGUGGCCGCCCAGAGUGGACAGUUGGAGGCCUUGAGGUUCUUAGCCAAGUACGGUGCUGACAUCAACACGCAGGCCAGCGACAACGCGUCUGCCCUCUACGAGGCCUGCAAGAAUGAGCAUGAGGAGGUGGUGGAGUUUCUGCUGUCACAGGGUGCCGACGCCAACAAGACCAACAAGGACGGCUUGCUCCCGCUGCACAUCGCCUCCAAGAAGGGCAACUACAGGAUCGUGCAGAUGCUGCUGCCGGUGACCAGCCGCACGCGCAUACGCCGUAGCGGCGUCAGUCCGCUGCACCUGGCGGCCGAGCGCAACCACGACGAGGUGCUGGAGGCGCUGCUGAGCGCGCGCUUCGACGUGAACACGCCGCUGGCCCCCGAGCGCGCGCGCCUCUACGAAGACCGGCGCAGCUCCGCGCUGUACUUCGCGGUGGUCAACAACAACGUGUACGCCACCGAGCUGCUGCUGCAACACGGCGCCGACCCCAACCGCGACGUCAUCAGCCCCUUGCUCGUGGCCAUCCGCCACGGCUGCCUGCGCACAAUGCAGCUGCUGCUGGACCACGGCGCGAACAUCGACGCCUAUAUCGCCACGCACCCCACCGCCUUCCCCGCCACCAUCAUGUUCGCCAUGAAGUGCCUGUCGCUGCUCAAGUUCCUCAUGGACCUGGGCUGCGACGGCGAGCCCUGCUUCUCAUGCCUCUACGGCAACGGCCCGCACCCGCCGGCCCCGCAGCCCUCCAGCAGGUUCAACGACGCGCCCGCGGCCGACAAGGAGCCCAGCGUGGUGCAGUUCUGUGAGUUCGUAUCUGCCCCAGAGGUGAGCCGCUGGGCGGGGCCCAUCAUCGAUGUCCUCCUGGACUACGUGGGCAACGUGCAGCUCUGCUCGCGGCUGAAGGAACACAUCGACAGCUUUGAGGACUGGGCCGUCAUCAAGGAGAAGGCAGAACCUCCAAGACCUCUGGCUCACCUUUGCCGACUGCGGGUUCGAAAGGCCAUUGGGAAAUACCGUAUAAAACUCCUAGACACCUUGCCGCUCCCAGGCAGGCUGAUUAGAUACCUGAAAUACGAGAACACCCAGUAACUGGGGCCACGGGGAGAGAGGAGUAGCCCCUCAGACUCUUCUUACUAAGUCUCAGGACGUCGGUGUUCCCAACUCCAAGGGGACCUGGUGACAGACGAGGCUGCAGGCUGCCUCCCUCUCAGCCUGGACAGCUACCAGGAUCUCACUGGGUCUCAGGGCCCAGAGCUUUGGCCAGAGCAGAGAACAGAAUGUGUCAAGGAGAAGAAUCAUUUGUUUACAAACUGAUGAGCAGAUCCCAGACCUUCUCUACCUUCAGGAAUGGCAGAAACCUCUAUUCCUGGGGCCAGGGCAGAGCUUGAGGUGUUCUGGGGAAGGUGGUGCUCAGAGCCUUCCCUGUGCCCCUCCACUUGUUCUGGAAAACUCACCACUUGACUUCAGAGCUUUCUCUCCAAAGACUAAGAUGAAGACGUGGCCCAAGGUAGGGGGUAGGGGGAGCCUGGGUCUUGGAGGGCUUUGUUAAGUAUUAAUAUAAUAAAUGUUACACAUGUGA